GGAGAUCGCGCCAGGCGAGGAGGAGAGCUCGGGCGAGCGGCGAGCACAGGCCACGGGAGCUGAGCGCAGCAGAGAGCAGCCGGAGUCCGCGCCUGACUCCGCGCGGGUCCUGAGCCGGCCGCAGCUUGCCAGGAUCCCCGGCGUCCUUCUCGCGCCGCUUCACGAAGAGGGCGCCUUCGCCGCUCGCCCAGCCGGAGUGCGCACGGGCCCGCUGGAAACCGCACUCGCCGCUCCCUGGGCAGGCCGGGGCACCCGGGCACGCAGGGCGCGCCUGGCGAGCGCCCCGGGAGGUGAGCAGUGGUCGCGGGCAGCGGGCAGCCGCUCAGCGGGGACCCGCCAGGGCUGGGGGCGCCCGAGUCCGAGGGGGACGACGCUUCUCGCACCCGCCACGACCCCCUUGGGCACCCACUCCCGGGUAAGCAAACCAAGCGCUCCUCCAUACCUUUCCCCCGCAGCACUCCGAAGAGUUCCCCUUUGCGGAGCGAAGCCUCGGGAGCCUGGGGACGCGGGGUUUAGGGGCACGCGGGACGGUGGUGGGUUGUGCAGUUCCUGCGGCCCUCCUCGAACUUUCCCGGCCCGGCCCCCCUCUUCUGCCCCCGCACCCCAGGCGACCCCCUCCUUCCCAGUCGUUCGGCGGAUGAGGUCAUGCCCGAGCCACCCCCGGGGGUGGGGGACUUGGAUCCCGCGACAGAGGGUGUGUGUGGUGGGCGGGGGGAAAGGGUGGCAAAAGGCAAAGAAAUGCGGCAGCGCCUAGUAAAUUGGGGAUGGGGGCAGAAGCCUGGCUUUGAGAACGGGUCCCAGGGGCGGCGGGGGGAGGGGGAGAACCGAGUUUGUUUACUGACCUGAGCUCCAGGCUGGGGGCUAGGGAGGAGGAAAGUCCUGUCCCCGGCCCCGAGGCACAUCUGCAACCGCCCGGAACAUCUGGCUGAGCUCGCGCACGAGCUCCACGCCUCCCACCCCCGGGGCUGAAGUGCCUCGGUGUCCCUCAAGGCCCUGGGCGUGCAGGGUCCGGCUCCAGGGGGUUAGCAGGAGGGAUCUCGAGUGCUCCCACCCACCCUUCCCACUUCCAAAACAACCCGUCUCCCGGGUGACCCGGCGCCGCGUGCGCAGCCAAGCAGACGUCUCUCGAAAGCCUCACGGCUGGGGUCAAAGCCGGGUGGCAGGCCCGGCCUCGCCCCGCCCCGCAGGUAACCUUGAAGCCGUCGCUCGGCGUCCCUGGUUGGCGGGGUCAGCUCCGUGAGCUGCGUGGCGGGAGGCUUCGGGACCCGCCCGUGCCGACCUUGCGCGCCGCGCGGACAAUCGGCCCCGGUGCACGGUGCCCGUGGGGCGUCGGGGUAGGGGGGACCCCGCAAGUCCUCGCCGGGCCGGCGUGGCCUGGUCCCAGCGGCCGGCUUUCCAGAGUCCUCCACAGACCGGGCCUAUGACCAUCUGUUGGCGGCGCUGGGCUGCGGCGCUGCGCUCGUGGUGUUCUCCCUGUGCACAGCCCCAGGCGGCCGCCUCCCGGGCCCGCUGCAGGCAGGGUAGCUCGGACCAACUUCGAGGAGGUGACCGCUCGCUCUCCAAAGGUGCUACGCCUGGCGCGGCCCACUACGCGCCCGGCCCCAAGCAAGGGGCCGGGCAGGUCAGGGCGGCCCACGGCAAGUGUCCUAUAGAACGACCAGGACACAGGGGGCACUCCCUCGACACGUCGUCCCAUCCCCAGACGGAGAAGCGGGGGCCCAGGAAGAGGACUUGACCCCAGCCCGCGACGCAGGAGGCAGCCGCGAUUCCCCCCUCCUCGAGCCCCGGCUUAGCGCCCCCUGGCGGGCUGGGGGCUUCAGGAGGCGCGUGCACCCUGACCCGCGAGCUCAGGCGGAAGGUGACCCCGUGGCCUGCGCGGCUGUCCCGGGCGCUCGUACAAGGGACAGGAACAGUCCGUCAGGACCCAGAGGCUCGGGCCAGGCGCUGCCUCCCCGCGCGACGAGCUUGGGCGGCGGAGGGAGAGCCUUGGGACAGCCGGGGCUGCACCGAAAGAGCUGGGCGGGGCUGGAGGCCUGGGUCCCCGUCCGCUGUGCGACCUAGGGGGCUCCUCCUCUCCCUGGGAGACCAGGCUGGACACAGAUCCCCCGCUGCGGCGUGCAGGACCAGCGGCGGCCGUGCAGGCGGAGGACUUCGGCGCGGCUCCUCCUGGGUGUGACCCCGGGCGCGCCCGCCGCGCGACGAUGAGGGCGCGGCCGCAGGUCUGCGAGGCGCUGCUCUUCGCCCUGGCGCUCCAGACCGGCGUGUGCUAUGGCAUCAAGUGGCUGGCGCUGUCCAAGACACCAUCGGCCCUGGCACUGAACCAGACGCAACACUGCAAGCAGCUGGAGGGUCUGGUGUCUGCACAGGUGCAGCUGUGCCGCAGCAACCUGGAGCUCAUGCACACGGUGGUGCACGCCGCCCGCGAGGUCAUGAAGGCCUGUCGCCGGGCCUUUGCCGACAUGCGCUGGAACUGCUCCUCCAUUGAGCUCGCCCCCAACUAUUUGCUUGACCUGGAGAGAGCGUCGGCUGACCUUCCCCUCCCACCCUCAGGGACCCGGGAGUCGGCCUUCGUGUAUGCGCUGUCGGCCGCCGCCAUCAGCCACGCCAUCGCCCGGGCCUGCACCUCCGGCGACCUGCCCGGCUGCUCCUGCGGCCCCGUCCCAGGUGAGCCACCCGGGCCCGGGAACCGCUGGGGAGGAUGUGCGGACAACCUCAGCUACGGGCUCCUCAUGGGGGCCAAGUUUUCCGAUGCUCCUAUGAAGGUGAAAAAAACAGGAUCCCAAGCCAAUAAACUGAUGCGUCUACACAACAGUGAAGUGGGGAGACAGGCUCUGCGCGCCUCUCUGGAAAUGAAGUGUAAGUGCCAUGGGGUGUCUGGCUCCUGCUCCAUCCGCACCUGCUGGAAGGGGCUGCAGGAGCUGCAGGAUGUGGCUGCUGACCUCAAGACCCGAUACCUGUCGGCCACCAAGGUAGUGCACCGACCCAUGGGCACCCGCAAGCACCUGGUGCCCAAGGACCUGGAUAUCCGGCCUGUGAAGGACUCGGAACUCGUCUAUCUGCAGAGCUCACCUGACUUCUGCAUGAAGAAUGAGAAGGUGGGCUCCCACGGGACACAAGACAGGCAGUGCAACAAGACAUCCAACGGAAGCGACAGCUGCGACCUUAUGUGCUGCGGGCGUGGCUACAACCCCUACACAGACCGCGUGGUCGAGCGGUGCCACUGUAAGUACCACUGGUGCUGCUACGUCACCUGCCGCAGGUGUGAGCGUACCGUGGAGCGCUAUGUCUGCAAGUGAGGCCCUGCCCUCCGCCCCACGCAGGAGCGAGGACUCUGCUCAAGGACCCUCAGCAACUGGGGCCAGGGGCCUGGAGACACUCCAUGGAGCUCUGCUUGUGAAUUCCAGAUGCCAGGCAUGGGAGGCGGCUUGUGCUUUGCCUUCACUUGGAAGCCACCAGGAACAGAAGGUCUGGCCACCCUGGAAGGAGGGCAGGACAUCAAAGGAAACCGACAAGAUUAAAAAUAACUUGGCAGCCUGAGGCUCUGGAGUGCCCACAGGCUGGUGUAAGGAGCGGGGCUUGGGAUCGGUGAGACUGAUACAGACUUGACCUUUCAGGGCCACAGAGACCAGCCUCCGGGAAGGGGUCUGCCCGCCUUCUUCAGAAUGUUCUGCGGGACCCCCUGGCCCACCCUGGGGUCUGAGCCUGCUGGGCCCACCACAUGGAAUCACUAGCUUGGGUUGUAAAUGUUUUCUUUUGUUUUUUGCUUUUUCUUCCUUUGGGAUGUGGAAGCUACAGAAAUAUUUAUAAAACAUAGCUUUUUCUUUGGGGUGGCACUUCUCAAUUCCUCUUUAUAUAUUUUAUAUAUAUAAAUAUAUAUGUAUAUAUAUAAUGAUCUCUAUUUUAAAACUAGCUUUUUAAGCAGCUGUAUGAAAUAAAUGCUGAGUGAGCCCCAGCCCGCCCCUGCAGUUCCCGGCCUCGUCAAGUGAACUCGGCAGACCCUGGGGCUGGCAGAGGGAGCUCUCCAGUUUCCAGGCAA